AAAUUCACAGCUGAAUUCUAUCAGACAUUGAAAGAACAUAGGUACAAAUCCUAUUGGCACUAUUCCACAAGAUAAAGAGAGAAUCCUUCCUAAAUCAUUCUGUGAAGUGAGUAUCACCCUAACACCAAAACCGGGAAAAGACAUAACCAAGAAAGGAAACUACAGACCAAUAUCCCUGACUAAUAUAGAUACAAAAAUCCUUAACAAAAUGCUAGCUAACCAAGUCCAGCAGCAUAUCAAAAACAUAAUCCACCAUGAUCAAGUGGGCUUCAUACUAGGGAAUCAGGGAUGGUUUAGCAUAAGCAAGUCAAUAAAUGUGAUACACCCCAUAAACAGAAUUAAAUACAAAAAUCACCUGAUUGUCUCAAUAGAUGAAGAAAAAGCAUUUGACAAAAGCCAGCAGCACUUUAUGAUUGAAAUCCUCAGCAAAAUCAGCAUAGAAGAGACAUACCUGAAUGUAAUAAAAGCCAUCUAUGGCAAACACACAGCCAACAUUAUACUGAAUGGAGAAAAGUUGAAAGCAUUUCCUCUGAGAACUGGAACAAGACAAGGAUGCCCACUCUCACCACUUCUGUUCAACAUAGUACUGGAAGUCCUAGCAAGAGCAAUCAGACAAGACAAAGAAAUAAAUGCUGUCCAUAUUGGUAAAGAGGAAGUCAAACUGCCACUAUUUGCUGAUGAUAUGAUCAGAUACCUAGAAAACCCUAAAGACUUUCAAAAAGCUCCAAGAACUGAUAAAUGAAUUCAGCAAAGUUUCAGGAUACAAAAUUAAUGUACACAAAUCAGUAGCUCUGCUAUACACCAACAGUGACCAAGCUGAGAAUCAAAUCAAGAACUCAAUCCCUUUCACAAUUGCCACAAAGUAAAUAAAAUACUUACAAAUAUACAUAACUCAGAGGGUGAAAGACCUCUACAAGGAAAACUACAAAACACUGCUGAAAAAAGUCACAGAUAACACAAACAAAUGGAAAUACAUCCCAUCCUCAUGGAUGGGGAAAAUCAAUAUUGUGAAAAAGACCAUACUGUUAAAAGCAACCUACAAAUGUAAUGCAAUUCUCAUCAAAAUGACACCAUCAUUCUUCACAGAACUAGAAAAAACAACCCUAAAAUUCAUAUGGAACCAAAAAAAGAGCCUGCAUAACCAAAGGAGGACUAAGCAAAAAAAGAAAAAAAAAAAUUUGGAGGCAUCACAUUACCCAACUUCAAACUAUACUAUAAGGCCAUAGUCACCAAAACAGCAUGAUACUGGUAUAAAAACAGGCACAUAGACCAAUGGAACAGAACAGAGAACCCAGAAAUAAACCUAAAUGCCUACAGCCAACUGAACUUCAACAAAGCAAACAAAAACAUAAAGUGGGAAAAGGACAGCCUAUUCAACAAAUGGUGCUGGCAUAAUUGGCAAGCCACAUGUAGGAGAAUGAAACUAGAUCCUCAUCUCUCACUUUAUACAAAAAUCAAGUCAAGGUGUAUCAAGGACUUAAAUCCAAGACCUGAAAGUGUAAAAAUUAUAGAAGACAACAUUGGAGAAAUCCUUCUAGACAUUGGCUUAGGCAAAGACUUCAUGACCAAGAACCCAAAAGCGAAUGCAACUAAAACAAAAAUAAAUAAGUGGGACUUAAUUAAACUAAAAUGCUUCUGCACAACAAAAGGAACAGUCAUCAGAGUAAACAGACAAUGCACAGAUUGGGAGAAAAUCUUUACAAUCUAUCCAUCCAACAGAGGACUAAUAUCCGGAAUCUCCUGGGAACUCAAACAAAUUAGCAAGAAAAAACAAAUAACCUCAUCAAAAAGCGGGGUAAGGACAUAAAUACACAAUUCUCAAAAGAAGAUAUACAAAUGGCCAACAAACAUAAAAAAUGAUCAACAUCACCAAUGAUCAGGGAAAUGUUAAUCAAAACCACAAUGUAAUACCACCUUACCCCCCCCCAAAAGAAUGAUCAUAAUCAAAAAACAAAAACUAAUAGAUGCUGGUAUGGAUGUGGUGAAAAGGGAACACUUCUACACUGCUGGUGGGAAUGUAAACUAGUACAACCACUAGAAAAAACAGUGUGGAGAUUCCUUAGGGAACUAAAAGUAGAACUAACAUUUGAUCCAGCAAUCCCACUACCCACAGAAAAAGUCAUUAUACAAAAAAGAUAUCUGCACAUGCAUGUUUAUAGCAGCACAAUUCACAAUUGCAAAAAUGUGGAACCAGCCCAAAUGUUCAUCAAUCAAUGAGUGGAUAAAGAAAUUGUGGUGUGUGUGUGUGUGUGUGUGUAUGCACACACAUACAUAUACAUACAUAUAUAUAUAUAUAUAGUGGAAUACUACUCAGUCAUAAAAAGGAAUGAAUUAACGGCAUUUGCAGCAACCUGAAUGGAAUUGGAGACUAUCAUUCUAAGUGAAGUAACUCGGGAAUAAAAAACCAAACAUUGUAUGUUCUCACUCAUAAGUGGGAGCUAAGCUCUGAGGAUAUAAAGGCAGAAGAAUGAUACAACGGACUUUGGGAACACUUGGAAAGGAUGAGAGGGAGGGCUGAGGGAUAAACGACUGAAAAUUGGGUUCAGUGUAAACUGCUCGGGUGAUACGUGCACCAAAAUCUCACAAAUCACCAAUAAAGAACUUACUCAUGUAACCAAAUACCACCUGUUCCACCAAAAACCAAUGGAAAUUUUAAAAAUUAUUAAAAAAUAAAAAAGAAUGAAGUGUGCUUACGAGAUCCAGAAAAUUGCCUCAAGUAGGGGAAAAAAAAACCCACAGAGUUACUUGCUUUACAGAGGAUGUAGAGAGAUCAGGGUAGAAUGUUUAUUCAAAUAAAUAAUAACAAAAAGUGUUUCAAACCUUGAGAAAAAAUAUAAAUAUCCAAAUACAAGAAUGUUAAAGAACACCAAGAAGACUCAAACUAAGUAAGAUGACUGCAAGGCAUAUAAUAAUCAAGCUCACAAAAGUCAAGGACAAAUAAAGGAUCCUAAAGUCGGCAAAAGAAAAAACCAAAUAACAUGUAAAGGACCUCUGACACAUCUGUCAGCAGACUUCUUAGCAGAAACCUUGCAAGCCAGUAAAGAACAGGAUGACAUAUUGAAAGUGCAGAAGGAAAAAACUGAAAGCUGAGAAUACUGCCAGCAAAGUUAUCUUUAACUUGAGAAUAUCCAGCAAAGUGAUCCUUAAAACAUGAAGUACAGAUAGACUUUCACAGAGAAAAGCUGAUGAAAUUCAUCAACAGACCUGUCUUUCAAGUAAUACUGUGUUCUUCAAUCUGAAAGGAAAUGACACAAAAAGGCAAGAAAUCAUCUGGAGAUCUAAAACUCACUGAUAAAUGUAGACACAUAGAUAAAUUUGGAAUAUUAUAGUACUGUACUUGUAUAUAAACCACUUAUAUCUUUACUGUGAAGACUAAAAGACAAAGCUAUCAAAAAUAAUAACAGGCUAGGCAUGGUAGUUCAUGCCUAUAAUCCCAGCAUUUUGGGAAACCAAGAUGGGUCAAUCACCUGAGAUCAGGAGUUCAAGACCAGCCCAGGCAACAUGGAGAAACCCCCUGUCUACCAAAAAUACAAAGAAAUAGCUUAGCAUGGUGGUGCAUUCCUAUGGUUCUAGCUACUCAGGAGGCUUAGGUAAAAGGAUCACUUGAGCCUGGGGGGCAGAGGUUGCAGUGAACCAAGAUUAUGUCACUGUACUCCAACUUGGGUGAUAGAGUGAGAUCCUAUCUCAAUAAUAAUAAUAAUAAUACGAGCAAUUUUAAGAGACAGACAAUAUAAAAAGAUAUAUAGAAACAACAAAAAGUCGUAAGGGGGGAUGGAGUUAAAGUGUAGCAUUUUUUCAGUUUUCUCUUUUUUUCUCCACCAUCGUCCGAGUUAAGUUGUCUUUAGUUUAAAGCAAUUCGUUAGAAUAGUCUUGCAAGUCUCCUCGUAUCCAUGAAGCAAAAGCCUGUAACAAAUAUACAAAAAAUAUAAAGCAAGGAAUUAAGAUAUACUACCAGAAAAAAAUCACUUAUACACAAAGAAGGACAGAAAUAAAGAAAAAAAGGACUUAGAAAACAAGCAGGAAGCAAAUAACACAAUGAAAGUUGUAAGUCCUUACCUAUCCGUAAUAAUAUUGGCAGUAAAUGGAAUAAAUGAUCUAAUCAAAAGACCUAGAGUGGCUGAAUGAAUCAAAAAAUAAGACCCAAAGUAGAUUCUGUGUACAAGAAACUAAUUUUACUGAUAAAGACAUACAACAGACCUAAAAUUAAAGAAUGGAAAAAAGAUAUUCUAUGCAAAUGGAAACCAAAAUAGAGCAGGAAUAACUAUACUUAUAUCAGACAAAGUAGAUGUCAAGCCAAAAACUGUAAAAAGAAACAAAGAAGGUCAUUAUAUAAUGAUAAAGGGGUCAAUACAGCAGAGGAUAUAAUAAUUGUAAAUAUAUAUGCAUCCAGCACCAGUGCACAGAGAUAUAUUUAAAAAUAUUAGUACAACUAAAGAGAGAGGUAGAUCCCAAAACGAUAACAAGUGUGGACUAUAACACCCCACUUUCAACAUGGUAAAGAUCAUCUAGACAAAAAAAUUAACAAAGAAAUAUCAGACUUAAUCUGCACCAUAAACUUGGAGGACCUCUUACACACUUACAAAACAUUUCACCCAAAAGGAGCAGAAUACACAUUCUUCUCCUCAGCACAUGGAACAUUCUCCAAGACAGACCAUAUGUUAGGCCACAGAAUAAAUCUCAACAAAUUUUUAAAAUAUUAAAAUUAUAUCAAGUAUCUUUUCUAACUACAAUGGAAUAAAACAAUAGAAAUAAAUAACCAGAAUUUGAAAACUAUACAAAUACAUGAAUAUUAAACAACAUGUUCCUGAAUGACCAAUGGGUCAAGGAAGAAAUUAAGAAGGAAAUUUUUAAAGUUUCUUGAAACAAAUGAAAAUGAAAGCACAACAUACCAAAACCUACAGAACACAGCAAAAGCAAUACUAAGAGGAAAGACUGUAGCAAUAAAUGCCUAAGUCAAAAAAGCAUAAAAACUUCAAAUAAACAACCUAAAAAUGCACCUUAAAGAAGUAGAAAAUUAAGAACAAAUCAAACCUUGAGUUAGUAGAAGGAAAGAAAUAAUAAAAAUCAGAGCAGAAAUAAAAUUGAAACUGAAAGACAAUGCAAAAGAUCAAUUAAACAAAAAGCUGGCUUUUUGAAAACAUGACAAAAAUCUACAAACCUUCAGCUAGACUAAGAGAAGACUCAAAUAAAUAAAAUGACAGAUGAAAAAUUAGACCGGGGUGUGGGGGGCAAGGGGAGGGAGAGCAUUAAGACAAAUAGCUAAUGCAUGUGGAACUUAAAACCUAGAUGAUGGGUUGACAGGUGCAGCAAACCACCAUGACACACAUAUACCUAUGUAACAAACCUACACUUUCUUCAGUUGUAUCCUAGAACUUAAAGUAACAUUUAAAAAAAAGAAAAAGAAAAAUGAGACAUUAUAAUAACACAGAAAAUAAAAAAAUUGUUACAGAUGAUUAUGAGCAGUGCCAAUAAAUUUAAAAACCUAGAAGAAAUGGGUAAAUUCCUAGACACAUACAACCUACCAAGAUUGAACCAUAAAGAAAUAGAAAACCUGAACGGACCAAUAAUAGGUAAUGAGAUAGCAAUGGUAAUAAAAUAUCUCCCAUCAAUGAAAAGCCCAUGAUCUUGUGGCUGCACUGCUGAAUUCUACCAAAAAUUUAAGGAAGAACUAAUACAAAUCCUACUCAAACCAUUCCAAAAAAUCAAAUAGGAGGGAAUGCUUCCAAACUCAUUCUUGGAAGGCCAGCCUUAUUCAGAUGUCAUAACCAAAGACACCCCAAAAAAGAACAUUAUACGCCAAUAUUACCAAUAAAUAUACAUGCAAAAAUCCUCAACAAAAUACUAGCAAACUGAAUCCAACAACAAAUUUCAAAGAUCAUUCACAUGAUCAAGUAGGAUUAAUCUUAGGGAUGCAAUGAUGGUUCAACAUACACAAAUCAAUAAACGUGAUAUAUCACAUAAAUAGAAUAAAGUACCAAAACCAUAUGGGCAUUUCAAUAGAUGCCAAAAAAAAUUCAAUGAAAUUUAACAUCGUUUCAUGAAAAAAACUCUCAACAAAAUGGAUAUAGAAGGAGCAUAUCUCAAAAGAAUAAAGGUCAUAUAUGACAAACACAGCUAGCAUCAUAUGAAAUGGGAAAAAACCUGAAAGCCUUUUGUCUAUGACCUGGAACAAGACAAAAUGACUGCUUUUACCACACACAAAAAAAUUAGUUUCAUGGGGUACAUGUGUGGGCUUUUUACAUAAAUACACUGCAUAAUGCUGGGGUUUGGGCUUCUACUGAACCCAUCACCCAAAUAGCUAACAUAGUACUCGAUAGGCAGUUUUUCAAUCAUUCCUCUCUUCCUCCCUCUUUUUGGAAAUCCUAGUGUCUAUUAUUUACAUCUUUAUGCCCAUAUGCACCCAUUUUUUGCCUCCCGUUUAUAAGUGAGAACAUGCAGCAUUUGAUUUUCUGUUUCUGCAUUCAUUCACGUAGGAUAAUAGCCUUCAGCUGCAUCGCUGAUGCUGAAAAGGGCAUGAUUUUAUUUUCUGUGGCUGUGUAGUAUUCCAUGGUGCUUUUACCACUUUUUUUUUUUUUUUUUUUUGAGACGGGGUCUCGCUCUGUUGCCCAGGCUGGAUGGAGUGCAGUGGCAGGAGCUCGGCUCACUGCAAGCUCUGCUUCCCGGGUUCACGCCAUUCUCCUGCCUCAGCCUCCUGAGUAGCUGGGACUACAGGCACCUGCCACCACGCCAGGUUAAUUUUUCUAUUUUUUUUUUUUUUUUUUUUGGUAGAGAUGGGGUUUCACUGUGUUAGCCAGCUUUCACCACUUUUAUUCAACAUAGUACUGGAAAUUCUAACAAGAGCAAUUAGGUAAGAGAAAGAAACAACACCCAAAUUGGGAAGGAAGAAGUUAAAUUCUCUUUAUUUGCAGAUAAUAUGAUUUUAUAUUUAGAAAAAAUCUAAAGAUCCCACCAAAAACGAACUGUAACUAAGAAACUGAUUUUAUUUAUAAAACCAACAUACAAAAAUCAGUAGCACAAAUGCCAACUGUGUAAAAAAAGAAAUCAAGAAAGCAAUCCCUUUUACAAUGACUACAAAAUAUAAAAUACCUAGAAAUAAACUAAACCAAAGAAAUGAAAGAUGUCUGCAAUAAAAAUUAUAAAACAUUGAUACAAAAUAAAGACAACACAAAAAUAGAAAAGUAUCCAUGUUCAUGAGUUGGACUAAUUAAUAUUGUUAAAAUGUCCAUACUACUCCAAGUUAUCUACAUAUACAUAAACUCAAUCUCUGUCAAAACACCAAAGACAUUCUUUAUGGAAACAGAAAAUAAACAGUCCUAAAAUUCAUAUGGAGCUACAGAAGGAUCAGAAUGGCCAAAGCAAUCCUGAAGAAAAAGAACUAAGCUGGGGCAUCAAAUUACCUGACUUCAAAUUAUACUAUAAACCUAUGGGGACAGGCGUGGUGGCUCACACUUGUAAUCCCAGCACUUUGGGAGGCCAAGGCGGGCGGAUCACGAGGUCAGGAGAUCGAGACCAUCCUGGCUAACAUGCUGAAACCCCGUCUCUACUAAAAAUACAAAAAAAUUAGCCCAGUGUGGUGGCGGGCACCUGUGGUUCCAGCUACUCGGGAGGCUGAGGCAGGAGAAUGGCGUGAACCCAGGAGAAGGAGCUCGCAGUGAGCCAAGAUUGCACCACUGCACUCCAGCUGAGCAAGACUCCGUCUCAAAAAACAAACAAACAAACAAGCAAACAAAAAACCUGUGGUAACCAAAACAGCAUGGUACUGGCAUAUGAAUAGACACCACAAAAUAGAGAACUCAUAAAUAAAUCUAUGCAUUUAUAGUCAACUUAUUUUCAAAAAAGGAGCCAAGAACACACACUAUAGAAAGGACACUCUCUGUAAUAAAUGUUGUUGGGAAAACUGGGUAUCCAUACACAGAAGAAUGAAACUAGACAUAUCUAUCUCUCACCAUAUACAACACUCAAAUCAAAAUGGAUUAAAGACAUAAAUCUAAGACCUGAAAUUGUGAAGCUACUAGAAGAAAACUUUGGGAAAAAGCUUCAGGACAUUGGUCUGAGCAACGAUUUCUUGAGUAAGACCUCAAAGCACAGGCAAAGGAAAAAUGGGCAAGUGAAAUCACAUCAGCUAAAAAGCUUCUGCACAGCAAAGGAAACAAUCAUAAAAUGAAGAGACAACCUAGGUAACAAGAGAAAAUAUUUACAAAGUAUUCAACUGACGGGAUUAAUAAUAAAAAUAUGUAAGAAAUUCCAACAACUCAAUAGUAAAAAAUCAAAUAAUCUGAUUUAAAAAUGGGCAAAAGAGCUGAGUAGACAUUUCUCAAACUAAGACGCACAAAUGGACAACAGAUAUAUAAAAAGUAUUCUAAAUCGCUAAUCAUCAGGUAAUUGUAUAUCAAAAUAGCAAUGAGAUAUCAUCUUACCCCAGUUAAAAUGGCUAUUAUCAAAAAGACAGAAAAUAAAAACUGCUGGUAAGGAAGUGAAGAAAGAGGUAUCCUUGUAAAUUGCUCGUGGGGAUAUAAAUUAGCAUAGCCAUUAUGAAAAACAGCGUGGUAGUUCCUCCAAAAACUAAAACUACAAAUUCCCUAAGAUCCAGCAAUCUCACUAUUGGGUAUAUAUCCAAAAGAAAGGAAAUCAGCAUAUCAACGAGCUAUCUGCACUCACAUAUUUAUUUGCAGCACUGAUCACAAUAGACAAGAUAUGGAAUCAACUUAACUGUCCAUCAAUAAAUAAAUGGAUAAAAAAUGUGAUAUAUAUAUAUAUAUAAUAAAAUAUUAUUCCACCAUAGAUUAAGAUUAACCUAACACUUAUUUAACUUUUCAGAUGUUAGCCAACAUAUUGUUUUUAUUGUACACCCAUUUGGUUUGUUGUCCUACAACAUGUAACUGAAAACAUCUUACUUGAUAUAGCAAUCUAAUAUUGUUGAUUAUUUUCAGAAUUAUAGGAUACUGUGAAAAACUGUAACUCACAAAAAAACACACAAAAAUUAAAAAUGACUUCACUUUAUGCGAAAUAGAUAAGGUUUGUUAAGUAUUGUAAUCACAUUCAAAAAUAACUCUUUAAGCUUAAAAUAAGCCAAUACUUCUUCAAAGCAAGGUCUCCAAAUCUAAAAUAUGCCUACAUAAUGCUUUGGAGAAACACUUAAUGUAUGUAUUCGUGAGUGUGUAUGCAUAUACAGAGAAUUAUAUCUGUGAGUUAUGUGAUUGGAUAGAGGUGUGUAUUUGGAAUUAAGAAUCUAUGGAUAGGAAUUUCUGGAACUGUACACAGAAUUCAUAGUUUUAUACAUGUGCAUGUGCUUGGAGAUAUAUAUAUAUAUACAUACAUACACAUUUGCAUAUGGUCGUAAAGGAUUCAUGUCUCCAUAAAUGUAUACACAUGGUAUUUCUAUGUUAAUUUGUAUGUUUCCAAAGAAUGUGAGAAAUGUCUGAAAGAUGGAAAACAGAUGGAGCAAGAGAGCUGAGGGGAGGGGCUAGAGAGCUUGAAGGAUCCAGCCAGCAGAGACAGGAAGAGAGAAAAGGCCACCUACAGGUUCCACUGUUGUGAAUUGUGGAAAGGGAAGGAGGAGCCCAGGAGGGGCCCCAAGAAAAGAAAGGCAGAUCUGCUCUGUGAUUAGAAUGGAAGACAUCACUACUAAGAGGAAACUAACACUGUAGUCUUGUGCAGAAAAAGGGCAGAGACUACAGCCACUGCAUCAGGGACUGGUGGCAGCCCAACGUGGCUGAGGGGUGGCCGCCACCAACAGGGAGGUAGACGGCCAGCGAGCGAAGCGCUGGGGACACCGCUGCAGUGCUCUUUGCCUGUCUCGCCGCGCUCCUACACACGCUCCUCAUCUAUGGAUCCUACCCUCCCCGCUCUUGCAAGCAGUCACUCAGCGAGUCGCCUGUUGACCCUCCUUCGCCACAGGCUCACAGCAGAGGCAGCAUCGAGGUAUCCGAUUUCGGCACGUGAGGCCCGCGAUCCCCGGCGGUGGACGCCAGGCAGGGCAUGAAGACCCCCAACGCACAGGAAGCCGAAGGGCAACAAACCAGGGCAGCUGCAGGACGGGCCACUGGGUCUGCAAACAUGACAAAGAAAAAAGUCUCCCAAAAGAAGCAGAGAGGCCGACCUUCAUCCCAGCCCCGCAGGAACAUCGUGGGCUGCAGAAUUUCUCAUGGAUGGAAGGAAGGAGAUGAGCCCAUCACGCAGUGGAAAGGAACCGUUCUGGAUCAGGUGCCUAUAAAUCCCUCUCUUUAUCUGGUGAAAUAUGAUGGAAUUGACUGUGUCUAUGGACUGGAACUUCACAGAGAUGAAAGGGUUUUGUCUCUUAAAAUUCUUUCUGACAGGGUGGCAUCAUCUCACAUUAGUGAUGCCAACCUUGCAAAUACCAUAAUUGGCAAAGCAGUGGAACACAUGUUUGAGGGAGAGCAUGGUUCUAAGGAUGAAUGGAGGGGGAUGGUCUUAGCUCAAGCACCUAUCAUGAAAGCCUGGUUUUAUAUUACCUAUGAGAAAGAUCCUGUCUUGUACAUGUACCAGCUUCUAGAUGAUUAUAAGGAAGGUGACCUCCGCAUCAUGCCAGAAUCCAGUGAGUCUCCUCCAACAGAGAGGGAGCCAGGAGGAGUUGUAGAUGGCCUAAUAGGUAAGCAUGUGGAAUAUACCAAAGAAGAUGGCUCCAAAAGGAUCGGCAUGGUCAUUCACCAAGUGGAAACCAAACCCUCUGUGUAUUUCAUCAAGUUUGAUGAUGAUUUCCAUAUCUAUGUCUACGAUUUGGUGAAAAAGUCCUAACUGUUAGGGUAAAAUUUGGCACAUGUGUGGAAACAAAUGUAUAAUUUGUAGACAUGCAAAAAAUGUUGCCUUUCAGUGUACUGAAAGCUUAUGGAAUCCCUGAUAACUAAACAUCUUUGCCAGCAUUAACUGUUGUUUUGCUCUAAAAAAUACAAAUUUGUGAAUACAUGA